ACAGUUACGCGCCGCACGGAUCAUGGCCGCAGCCGCUCUGGGGCAGAAGCAUGGCUGCAAGGCUGAGCAGUCUAGAUGUCGCCACCCAAAGGCAAUCUGGGGACCCACGCUCUGAUCACCCCGGAAUCCCUGGAGCCUCACACCAGCAAGACCACGCUGCAGGCCCAUCUCCCAGCAACUCACCUAGCGACAAGUGACCACGCCCAUUCACGUCCAUCUUCCAGAAUCAGUGCCAACUCACCCAGCUCACAGGGCAGGCCAGGCCAGGCCACUCUGUCUCUCUCAACCUCACGCCCCAACGCCUCCCCACAGGGCUGGGGAAAGAGGCCUUGUGAGGUCAAAGGUCACCAGAGAGGGCCCAGCCUGCUGGACACAGCCAGACCUGCUCUUCCUACUCCCCUCUGGGAGGACCCGCCUGAGCCUCAUGCAGUGAGGACUGCAGUGGCUCCCCAGGCCCCUGUAGCUGCCCCUCAGCCCCAGGGGCUGAAGGGAAUUGGAGUCACUGCCAAAAUGGGUUUGUAUUUCAGAUCUGGGCACGAAAGCUUCUCUCUGUCCCUUGGCUUCUGUGUGGUCCCAGAAGAUAUGCCUCCUCCAGUUUCAAGGCUGCAGACCUGCAGCUGGAAAUGACACAGAAGCCUCAUAAGAAGCCUGGCCCCGGCGAGCCCCUGGUGUUUGGGAAGACAUUUACCGACCACAUGCUGAUGGUGGAAUGGAAUGACAAGGGCUGGGGCCAGCCCCGAAUCCAGCCCUUCCAGAACCUCACGCUGCACCCAGCCUCCUCCAGCCUCCACUACUCCCUGCAGCUGUUUGAGGGCAUGAAGGCGUUCAAAGGCAAAGACCAGCAGGUGCGCCUCUUCCGCCCCUGGCUCAACAUGGACCGGAUGCUGCGCUCAGCCAUGCGCCUGUGCCUGCCGAGUUUCGACAAGCUGGAGUUGCUGGAGUGCAUCCGCCGGCUCAUCGAAGUGGACAAGGACUGGGUCCCCGAUGCCGCCGGCACCAGCCUCUAUGUGCGGCCUGUGCUCAUUGGGAACGAGCCCUCGCUGGGUGUCAGCCAGCCCACGCGCGCGCUCCUGUUCGUCAUUCUCUGCCCAGUGGGUGCCUACUUCCCUGGAGGCUCCGUGACCCCGGUCUCCCUCCUGGCCGACCCAGCCUUCAUCCGGGCCUGGGUGGGCGGGGUCGGCAACUACAAGUUAGGUGGGAAUUAUGGGCCCACCGUGUUAGUGCAACAGGAGGCACUCAAGCGGGGCUGUGAACAGGUCCUCUGGCUGUAUGGGCCCGACCACCAGCUCACCGAGGUGGGAACCAUGAACAUCUUUGUCUACUGGACCCACGAAGAUGGGGUGCUGGAGCUGGUGACGCCCCCGCUGAAUGGUGUUAUCCUGCCUGGAGUGGUCAGACAGAGUCUACUGGACAUGGCUCAGACCUGGGGUGAGUUCCGGGUGGUGGAGCGCACGAUCACCAUGAAGCAGUUGCUGCGGGCCCUGGAGGAGGGCCGCGUGCGGGAAGUCUUUGGCUCGGGCACCGCUUGCCAGGUCUGCCCAGUGCACCGAAUCCUGUACAAAGACAGGAACCUCCACAUUCCCACCAUGGAAAAUGGGCCUGAGCUGAUCCUCCGCUUCCAGAAGGAGCUGAAGGAGAUCCAGUACGGAAUCAGAGCCCACGAGUGGAUGUUCCCGGUGUGAAGCUGCAGGCUGUGCUCCAGAUCCACCGACCCGUAGCAUCUCGUCACGCCAGCACUCGCCUCCCUACCAAUGACUCACCUGAAGUGCAAUACGAAAUAAAAGGCCAGCGGGCGGCGUCUGGGUCUCUGGCGCCCCCAUGUGGUUGCGACACUCCCAAAGCCGUAAGGGCCGACCCAGGCAUCUUGGCCCCCAGCCCCUCGUCGCGGGUUCAGGUCCGCCCAUUACUCCUUGUCGUGCGGUCAAGGAUACACCUUGGCCCCGAUUCCGGAUCUCUCCGUUCUCAGGCCAGACCCCUGGUGCUGCCGUUGAUUUUUUUUUCUCUGUCUUUGCUGCAAUUUUGAAAUAAAAUGCCAAAGAACACA